AGGGGGUAUCUCACUCCGUUGCCCAGGCUGCUGGAGUGCAGUGGCGCAAUAUCACUGCAACCUCCACCUCCUGGGUUCAAGCGAUUCUCAUGCCUCAGCCUCCCGAGUAGCUGGGAUUACAGACACGCACCACGACGCCCGGCUAUCUGCUGGGAUUUUGUGGAAAGAAGCUGCAGCAGCCAAAGCUUGGGAGAGACAAGGGGCAGGGCAUGCUUGCAAGGGGUUAACCAUGACAGGUUACAAUUACGACAAGAAGCUCUUUAGGCAGUGAGGCUCCAGAGAGAGCUUCUGUGGGUUGAUAGUCAAGCAUUCCCCAGGUAGAGCACGGAGAAAGGAGGCUCAGGACAAUGGUCCUGGGACCUUGUUUCCAUCCACGACUCGAGGCAUCUGAGACUUGCUAGGGACUACACACACUCUAGAGAAACAGUAGGGGAGAGUGGCCUAUGACCAGCCCCAACCUAUGCUCAGGUUGUCCUUUCCCGGAUCUCAGAGAAGGUGUACUACAUGUUUGUAUUGCCCCUUAUAGUUUACAAAGCACCUUCCCAAACAUUAUACCCUGUCACUCAAGGUCAACAUGAUCACUGUUGAGGUUUAUUCCUGCCCAGAUCCAGGUAUCUGGUGCAGUCACCUUGCUAUCCCCUUGCCUAGAUCUUUCAUCUCACUAUUGGCAACUUCCCUCAGCAUAUUAACACACAGGUUUCUACCAUGGUUAAUUUUAAAAUUAAAAAAGCCCUUGAAUCUCAAACCUCCUUAAAUAACUGUCUUCUCUUUUAGCAGGAACUCUGCCAUGUCUUUCUCUGCACUCCUCUAGCCUUGUGGACUGCCUUUGUUUUGUACCACUUUUUUUGUUCUGUUUUGUUUAUUUGUUUGAGAGGGAGUCUUGCUCUGUCACCUAUGCUGGAGUGCAGUGGUGCGAUCUUGGCUCACUGCAACCUCCACCUCCUGGGUUCAAGCCAUUCUCCCGCCUCAGCCUCCUGAGUAGCUGGGAUUACAGGCAUGCACCACCACACCCAGCUAAUUUUUUUGUAUUUUUAGUAGAGGCAGGGUUUCGCCCUGUUGGUCAGGCUGGUCUCGAACUCCUGAUCUUAGGGGAUCCACCUGUCUUGGACCUCCCUAAGUGCUAGGAUUACAAGCGUAAGCCACCGCGCCAACCUGUUUUUUUUUUUUUUUUUUUUGAUGUAGUCUCGCUCUGUCUUCCAGGCUGGAGUGCAGUGGCAUGAUCUCGGCUUACUGCAACUUCUGCCUCCCGGGUUCCAGUGAUUCUCCCACCUCAGCCUCCUGAGUAGGGGAUUACAGGCGCGCACCACCACGCCCAGCUAAUUUUUUGUAUUUUUAGUAGAGACGGGGUUUCACCACGUUGGCCAGGCUGGUCUCGAACUCCUGACCUCAAGUGAUUUGCCUGCCUUGGCCUCCCAAAGUGCUGGCAUUACAGGUGUGAGCCACCGCAUCCGGCACUUGUACCACUUUUCUGAAACCAUUCUGACAUAGACAUUGGUGAUGUCUCGAGACCAGCUCCUAAAUCCGCAGCACACUCUCCAACCCCAGUGUUACCUGGCCCUGUUAUUUUUAACACUGGAAACUGUCCCCACAUUCUUGAAUCCCCCCAAUCUUGGCCUUCAGGGCCCACCUUCUCCUGGCCUUCUUCCUGCUCCCAGAGUGCCUUCCAGACUUCUGGGGCUUUGCUCCCUGGCUCAGUGCUGGCCUACACCCCCAGCACCCUUGAAAACUGAUGAUCUCAAUCUCUCUCCAUCUAGUGCUUUUUUUUUUUUUUUUUUUUUUUUUAAGGAAAGAGUCUCGCUCUGUCACCCAGGCUGGAGUGCAGUGGUGCAAUUACAGCUCACUGCAACCUCUGCCUCCUGGGUUCAAGGGGGUUCUCGUGCCUCAGCCUCCCAAGUAGCUGGGAUUACAGGAAUGCAUACCGCACCCAGCUAAUUUUUGUAUUUUUAGUAGAGAUGGGGUUCCACCAAUUUGGCCAGGAUGGUCUUGAACUCUUGGCCUCAAGUAAUCUGCCCACCUUGACCUCCCAAAGUGCUGGGAUUACAGGCAUGAGCCACCUUGCUUGGCCUCCAUUUAGUGCUUGAGAGGUAUCUUCCUCUGGUGUUUCCCAAAGCAACUAUUUUCCCCAAGCAGUCUCCCCCUAUCAUGUUAACAGUGUCACACGCACGCUGGUGCCCAGUCCAGCAUUAUCCCUUGUCCCCACCACCUGACCUCAUCUGUAUGAAAUUUUGCCAGUUCUUUCCCAAACCCUGCCCAGGCCUUCCUACUGGUUCCAAGCCUCAGGCCUUUCAGGCUUCAUCCUCCCAGUCCCCAGCUGCUCCCCACAUUGCACCCAGAGGUGGCAAGAGAAGGGUCCAUACUUAAGGUAGGAGGGGGUUGCAGGGCUGAGGCAUAGGGGGCUGGAGUAUGCUGGGGAGUAGAGGCAGAGCAGGGACUAGAGUGAGGCCAGAGAGGGACCCAAGGCACAAAGGGAAGGAGGCUGUCACCCUCAGGGCUGUGUACUUGCUGUUUGUGCCCUUCAUUUGUGCCCUACGUGGCUCUCUGUCCUCAUCCUAGUCCUGGCCCUUGCUUAUGGGGACAGACGGGUCCAAGGGAGGAGGGUGGCGAAGUGCUCUUCUCCACACCUGUGGGGACAGAUGCUGAGAAUGGAAUUCUACAGAGACAGUGGACAGGCUUGGUAGUGAACUUUCCAACAACCUAGAGCUCUCAUUCCUGGUGUGGGGGCCAGAAGACUCCCGAAGGACAACAGUUUUGUCAGGUGCCCUUGGUCUGGGCCAGGGACUCAGCAUUAGAACUGGGCAUCUGGGUAGAAGACGGUCUGUGGGGCCAUAGGGUGCCACGUGGGCCCCUUAACUUGAUAGGGAAGGAGGGCUCCCUGCCUGGUUUAUGCAGGGUGUAGUGGGAAAAGGCCUGAAGGGCGCCCUCUCCCAUUUCCCACACACUUAUUUGAGGGUCUAACCCGAGGCAGACACUGCCUGGUGCUCCUGCCCGGCUGCAUUAUGCAGAUCUCUGGGGCAGGUGUUCCCAGGUGCGAACUUGAGACAAAGGAACGAGGAAGCACGGCCUCCCUGAGCACAGGUAACCCGAGGCCUGGCUCCCCCUGCGCUUGUGGGCCGGCCUUGGGGGAGGGGGACGCGCACCCACAGAAGGACUCAGAGGGCUUCACGAGGAGAAAACUGCAGUCCGGGAUGGCUCAGUCGGCCCCUCCAAAGUCGCGCAGCUGGUUCGGGCCGAGCCCCGACUGCGAGAGUGAGGCACAUGGCCCCUGCAGACCGGGCCUCGGAGGGUCCCAGGCUUGAGGACCCGUCGGCCCCUCAACCCCUUGGAAAGUGCCCCCCUGGCUUAGUCAUGGCGAAGCUGGAGACGCUGCCUGUGCGCGCUGACCCAGGGCGGGAUCCUCUCCUGGCCUUUGCCCCACGGCCCUCCGAGCUUGGACCCCCGGACCCCCGCCUGGCCAUGGGCAGCGUGGGCAGUGGGGUGGCCCAUGCCCAGGAGUUUGCCAUGAAGAGCGUGGGUACCCGCACAGGGGGUGGGGGCAGCCAGGGCAGUUUCCCUGGCCCCCGAGGCAGUGGCAGUGGGGCCAGCAGGGAGAGGCCGGGCCGCUACCCCUCAGAGGACAAGGGUCUCGCCAACUCCCUCUACCUCAAUGGUGAGCUGCGGGGCAGUGACCACACCGAUGUCUGUGGCAACGUGGUUGGCAGCAGCGGAGGCAGCAGCAGCAGUGGUGGCAGUGACAAAGCCCCACCGCAGUAUCGUGAGCCCAGCCACCCACCCAAGCUCCUGGCCACCUCUGGCAAGCUAGACCAGUGCUCAGAACCACUAGUUCGGCCGUCGGCCUUCAAGCCUGUCGUACCCAAGAAUUUCCACUCCAUGCAGAAUUUGUGCCCCCCGCAGACCAAUGGGACUCCUGAGGGACGGCAGGGCCCUGGUGGCCUCAAAGGCGGACUGGACAAGUCUCGGACCAUGACUCCAGCGGGUGGGAGUGGGAGUGGCCUCUCAGACUCAGGCCGGAACUCCCUCACAAGCCUGCCCACCUACAGCUCCAGCUACAGCCAGCACCUGGCACCCCUCAGUGCCUCCACCAGCCACAUUAACCGCAUUGGCACUGCCAGCUAUGGUAGUGGUAGUGGCGGCAGCAGCGGUGGGGGGUCGGGCUACCAGGACCUGGGGACCUCCGAUAGUGGACGGGCCUCCAGCAAGAGUGGGUCGUCGUCAUCUAUGGGGCGGCCAGGCCACCUGGGCUCUGGGGAGGGCGGAGGUGGAGGCCUGCCUUUCGCGGCCUGCUCACCGCCCUCCCCCAGUGCACUCAUCCAGGAGCUGGAGGAGCGGCUGUGGGAGAAGGAGCAGGAGGUGGCAGCUCUGCGGCGCAGCCUGGAGCAGAGCGAGGCGGCUGUGGCCCAGGUACUGGAGGAGCGGCAGAAGGCGUGGGAGCGGGAGCUGGCCGAGCUGCGGCAGGGCUGCAGCGGGAAGCUACAGCAGGUGGCCCGACGUGCCCAGCGCGCCCAGCAGGGCCUACAGCUGCAGGUGUUGCGGCUGCAGCAGGACAAGAAGCAGCUGCAGGAGGAGGCGGCCCGGCUGAUGCGGCAGCGGGAAGAGCUGGAGGACAAGGUGGCCGCCUGCCAGAAGGAGCAGGCCGACUUCCUGCCCCGGAUAGAGGAAACUAAGUGGGAGGUGUGCCAGAAGGCUGGCGAGAUCUCCCUCCUGAAGCAGCAGCUGAAGGACUCGCAGGCGGAUGUGUCGCAGAAGUUGAGUGAGAUCGUGGGACUGCGCUCGCAGCUGCGGGAGGGCCGGGCUUCGCUGCGGGAGAAGGAGGAGCAGCUGCUCAGCCUGCGGGACUCCUUCAGCAGCAAGCAGGCCAGCCUGGAGCUGGGCGAAGGCGAGCUGCCUGCCGCCUGCCUCAAGCCGGCGCUGACCCCCGUGGACCCGGCCGAGCCACAGGAUGCUCUGGCCACCUGCGAGAGCGACGAGGCUAAGAUGCGCCGUCAGGCCGGGGUGGCCGCUGCCGCCUCCUUGGUUUCCGUGGACGGGGAGGCGGAGGCUGGCGGGGAGAGCGGGACGCGGGCCCUGCGGCGGGAGGUGGGGCGGCUGCAGGCCGAGCUGGCGGCUGAGCGGCGGGCCCGGGAGCGCCAGGGUGCCAGCUUCGCCGAGGAGCGCCGCGUGUGGCUGGAGGAGAAGGAGAAGGUGAUCGAGUACCAGAAGCAGCUGCAGCUGAGCUACGUGGAGAUGUACCAGCGCAACCAGCAGCUGGAGCGCAGGCUGCGGGAGCGCGGGGCCGCAGGGGGUGCAAGCACGCCCACUCCCCAGCAUGGCGAGGAGAAGAAGGCCUGGACCCCCUCCCGCCUCGAGCGCAUUGAGUCCACAGAAAUCUGAUCGACCUGGGCACUCGGCAUUUUGACACAUGUCCUGUCAAAAGGCCAGAGUCCCCAGUGUCCCCUCCCCUCCAUCUCUCUUCCCCAUAGACCCCAUAACCCCAGACCAAAGAGGUUCUCUAAGCAGCUGUGACCAGGUUCCUCCCUCCCCACCUGCCCUCCUAGCUCCAGCACUGCCCCCGUGGCAGCCCACUUGGACCCCCCUAAAAGGAGGGAAUAGGAGGAGGGCAGGGUGAGUGGGGGCAAUCCUAGGUGGUGGGGGAGUCAUGCUCCCUUUCUCGGCACCCCCUUGUUGGAGAUGGAGGCAGCAGACGUGCAGUGCCAUAAGGUGCCCCAGUCCUUCUGGAGGCCUGGGCUGCUACUGUUGGCCACCCUGUGUCUAGUGAUGCUCUCUGUGCUCACCUCCUAGGCCAUGGAGCCUGAGGGGGCCUGCACCAGGUUUGCUGAAACUGACAGAGCCUGGGCUCCAGACCUCUCUCCCUCCUACAGUGCUCUCCCUCCCUGGGCAGAUUGGCAGGACAAGUGGGAGCAGAUGGCCUGCCUUUGGCUGAGAGGGCUACCUGCCCAGCCCCUCCCCCAACAAGAUCUCUUGGACUCAGGCCUCAGAGCCUGGCCUGGUUGUGAGUGUGUGUCCCUGUGUGUGUGUUGCGGGAGGGGAGGACUGGGGCUGGAAGUCCAGCACCCAGGGAAGAUCUGUCCUCCUGUUCUUGGGAAGCGUUGCCUGACGGCUUCUCGGCUCUACCCUCACCCUUCUGGCCAGGAUCCCGCAGGGCAACAGCCCCAUCUGCUUGGCUGACCCCACACCCAGGACCACUGUCCGGCUCUAACACAGCUAUUAAGUGCUACCUGCCUCUCAGGCACUCUCCUCGCCCAGUUUCUGAGGUCAGACGAGUGUCUGCGAUGUCUUCCCGCACUCUAUUCCCCCAGCCUCUUUCUGCUUUCAUGCUCAGCACAUCAUCUUCCUAGGCAGUCUCUUCCCCAAAGUCUCACCUUUUCUUCCAAUAGAAAAUUCCGCUUGACCUUUGGUGCACUGCCCACUUCCCAGCUCCACUGGCCCAAGUCUGAGCCGGAGGCCCUUGUUUUGGGGGCGGGGGGAGAGUUGGAUGUGAUUGCCCUUGAAGAACAAGGCUGACCUGAGAGGUUCCUGGCGCCCUGAGGUGGCUCAGCACCUGCCCAGGGUAGGCCUGGCAUGAGGGGUUAGGUCAGCCAAUGUCAGCUGCUUCUCUUGGGGCCCUCUCAGAGUCUAUCUCCCCAAGACAGGAAGGGAAAAGCAAAUUUCUAAUUCACCAGCAAUAAAAAUUGGAGGAGGCUUGGCCCUCAGCCCUUAUAUCUCUCUCUUUUUCACUCUCUUCCUCCCACCCCCAAGACUGAGUUUUGGGGGGCAAGGUGGAGAGAGCUGGCAACUACUGUGAGCAAGUCCCCUAGCCCCUGACCAGCCUCCUCCCAUGACUGGUGACUGUUUAAUGAGCUGUGCAUCCCCCACAAAAACAUGAGUGCCCCUCUGUGUGGCCUCUAACCCUCUGCACAGCCCUUCUGGGUGGUCCUCACCAGGUCUCUGAGCUGGGUGGGAGGCCAUCCUGGCGACCACUGCCCAUUCCAUUCACCCCUCACUGUACCUGCCCUAGAACCUGGGCCUAGGCCACAGGGGCAGGGAGAAGAGAAGGCAUUAGUAAGAAAAAAAUAGAAAAAAAUAUGAACAGACUCAGCUUUGGGACGUCCAACCACAAAAGAAAUUAUAUAUAAAUAUAUAUAAAUAUAUAUCUCUACCAUAUGUGAUGGAAAGACUUUUUGUUUUCCUUUCCCAAAGAAAUAAAACGGAAAAAGCCUCUUGAGUGGUA